ACCGCUAGCCCGCAGCGCUCGGCUUCCUGGUAAUUCUUCACCUCUUUUCUCAGCUCCCUGCAGCAUGGGUGCUGGGCCCUCCUUGCUGCUCGCCGCCCUCCUGCUGCUUCUCUCCGGCGACGGCGCCGUGCGCUGCGACACACCUGCCAACUGCACCUAUCUUGACCUGCUGGGCACCUGGGUCUUCCAGGUGGGCUCCAGCGGUUCCCAGCGCGAUGUCAACUGCUCGGUUAUGGGACCACAAGAAAAAAAAGUAGUGGUGUACCUUCAGAAGCUGGAUACAGCAUAUGAUGACCUUGGCAAUUCUGGCCAUUUCACCAUCAUUUACAACCAAGGCUUUGAGAUUGUGUUGAAUGACUACAAGUGGUUUGCCUUUUUUAAGGAUGUCACUGAUUUUAUCAGUCAUUUGUUCAUGCAGCUGGGAACUGUGGGGAUAUAUGAUUUGCCACAUCUGAGGAACAAACUGGUUAUUAAAUAGAGCAUCUGUUGAGGGACUCUUUUAAAACCACAGCCAUGAACAGACGUUGGGGCUAAGAGACAGAGCAGCCUGCGACAGUGUGGACCUACCUGUAGCAGCUAGCAAAGGCCUCUAGCAGCUACAGUCCCUUCUGGAGUCUUUAUUUGCAUGCAAAAUGCAAAGGAGUCCUGGUGACCUACCUCCAAGGCAGCUGCCCUCCUGAACACUCCCUUGGAAAACAGUAAACAUCAUUUUGGAAUGUGAACAACCAGAGACUACACAGGAGAAAGGAAAAAAAAAUUCUGAAGAUGCAAAAUCUUGGGUGGCUUCACCGUUCAGUUUUUUAAUAAAAGGAACAAUAUACAACACGUUGUUCUUUUUCUCUUUUGAAAUCCCUUCUAUUACAGUGAUUUUUUUCUAAGAUUGUCAGGAUUUGAAGUGUAUGUUUUGUUUUAUUCACAGCGUAAAUUUUAUUCACAGUUUAACUGUCUGCCUGAGUGUCUUUCCUUUCUCUAAUUACCUUGAGGAACCCAAGAGCCUGUUGUAAGGAGAAAAUAAGGCCCUUGGAUCUCUUGAGAUUCACAGAUAUAAGUUAUUGAAGGGAAGAUGGUCCUAUGGAGGACAUAUUUAAAGAAGGGAAAAAAGAGGCUUUCUCAGAUAUGUCAGACUGCUAUAGUAUACUUCUACAGAUUAUAGACCUCCAGUACCUCUGGCCAGAAAGAUGGUAUCGUAAACACCCUAUUUUUUUUCUUUUCUUUUUUCAUUAGGUACAAGCUUUGUGCUAAGAAGUUGACAUACUAUAAGCUACAAAAGUUCUGUAAAGUAGAUAUAACUAGUUUCAUUUUAUAGAUAGAGAAAAUUAAUCUCUUACAGUGCUAAGCUCACAGAGUUUCUAACUGUAAAAUGCUAGAACUUGUCUUUCAAGCCUAAAGACUUCCUUGGGGCUAAAUAGUGAAAAAAGCCAUUUCACAAAUAAGUAAAUGGUAUUUAGAGGCAUAUUUGGAUUUCCUGGUAAAUUCCAGUCUGUGAGCAUCAUGAAUAUUAGUUUAAUGUUGCAUGGGCUCAUGUUGAAGUUUUAAGAGAAGAACUGCCUUGAAGCUUAGGUUUCCUUAGCUAUUAGGCUACUGACUUUCUUGCCUAAACCAGGGUUUUUUCAUUGAAGACCAAAACUUACCUUCUCCUUCAGUUUGUAGUUUGGAAAUUGGUAGAAGAGCUUUGUAAACUUCAAAUUAAGUACAAACUAAGUGUCAUAGUCAAAUUUACUAAUCUUAAUUACAGUAUUGUUCAACUGAUUGCUAUCUUCUAGCUCUUUCCUGCCGAAUAAUGGUCUUGUUUCCUGCUCUGUUGGUUUAGAGCUGACUUCUUUCAGCUUUGGUAAGCCUGAAAUUAUGGGGUUAUGUUUAAUUCAUAUUGUCUGGGUGGACUUUCCUCUCUUGCAUUUCUGCUUGAAUAGAAGAAUUUUUCUCUAGAGAGUAGUUUGUCAUCCUUACUCUGUUGAUUCAGAUGACUCUUUGUAUGAUCUGAGAGGUAUACUGUUCUGCUAUUCUGAGAAGAAGUAUUUCAGAAAGAUGAAUUAAGAGUACAGUGGACUGCUCCCACCUGGAAACUUUUAUCUAUCUCACCUCUGGACCUGAUAAAUUCUUUAUCACUCAGGACCUUGAUGACGCUGCUCUCUGAAACCCUCCCCAGCUCUCUCUAUUACCGUGAGAAACAUCAGAACUUUGGUUCCCAUUGCAUAUCGCAGGUACCUCUGCUUUCAUGCCAUGCUGUAAUGGAGUGAUUGGGUAGCAUGUUUUCAUCUCUUUCCAGAUUGAAAAUCUGUAUUUCUCCCUGUAUAUCUUCAACACCUAAUGCACAUAGAACUUUGUAGGUACCUGGAAAAUGCACCACAGUUUUCUUUUCUUUUUGCAGACUUUUCACAAGUAUUACCAACUUACAAAGAAUUAAUUUUGUAGGAUUCUAGAAAGACAAAUCAGGAAUGGUGCCAUAUACAUCUUUUUUGAUUCCCUGCUCUAAAGAAUAUUAUCAGGUUACCUUCCUGCAGAGUUUUAAAAGAAUUGCAUAUUUCAAGCUGACUUUCAGGAUGUAAAUAUAACCAAAGCAACUGAUAUGUAAAAAAUAUAUUCAAUGGCAUUCCUAGAUUUUCUUCUAGGGUGUUUUAUUGUUUUGGGUUUUACAUUUAAGUCUUUAAUCCAUCUUGAGUUAAUUUUUGUAUAGGUAUAAGAAAGGGGUCCAGUUUUAAUUUUCUGCGUAUGGCUAGCCAGUUCUCCCAGCACCAUUUAUUAAAUAGGGAAUCCUUUCCCUAUUGUUUGUUUUUGUACGGUUUGUCAAAGAUUAGAUGGUUGUAGAUGUGUGGUCUUAUUUCUGAGAUCUUCAUUCUCUUCCACUGGUCUAUGUGUCUGUUUUUGUACCAUGCUUUUUUGGUUACUGUAGCCUUGUAGUAUAGUAUGAAAGAUAGCAUGAUGCCUCCAGGUUUGUUCUUUUUGCUUAGGAUUGUCUUGGCUAUACGAGCUUUUUUUUGGUUCUAUAUGAAUUUUAAAAUAGUUUCUUCUAAUUGUGUGAAGAAUGUUAAUGGUAGUUUAAUGGGAAUAGCAUUGAAUCUGUGAAUUGCUUUGGGCAGUAUGGCCAUUUUCAUGAUAUUGAUUCUUCCUAUCCAUGAGCAUGUAACGUUUUUCCCUUCGUUUGUGUCCUCUCUCAUUUCCUUGAGUAGUGGUUUGUAGUUCUCCUUGAAGAGAUCCUUCACUUCUUCUGUAUUCCUAGAUAUUUUAUUCUCUCUGUAGCUAUUGGGAAUGGGAGUUCAUUCAUGAUUUUGCUCUCUGCUUGCCUUUUGUUGGUGUAUAGGGAUCCUGGUGACUUCUGCACAUUGAUUUUGUAUCCUGAGACUUUACCGAAGUUGCUUAUCAGCUUAAGAAGCUUUUGGGCUGAGAUGAUGGGGUUUUCUAGAUAUAGGAUCAUGUUAUCUUCAAACAAAGACAAUUUGACUUCCUCUCUUCCUAUUUGAGUACGCUUUAUUUCUUUCUCUUGCCUGAUUGCCCUGGCCAGAACUCCCAAUACUAUAUUGAAUAAGAAUGGUGAGAGAGGGCAUCCUUGUCUUGUGCCAGUUUUCACGGGGAAUGCUUCCAGCUUUUGCCCAUUCAGUAUGAUAUUAUCUGUGGGUUUCUCAUAAAAAGCUCUUAUUAUUUGAGAUACGUUCCUUCAAUACCUAGUUUAUUGAGAGUUUUUAACAUGAAGCGAUGUUGAAUUGUAUCGAAGGCCUUUUCUGUGUCUAUUGAGAUAAUCAUGUGGUUUUUGUCUUUAGUUCUGUUUAUGUGAUGAAUGACGUUUAUUGAUUUGCAUAUGUUGAACCGGCCUUGCAUCCUGGGGAUGAAGCCAACUUGACUGUGGUAGAUAAGCUUUUGGAUGUGCUGCUGGAUUUGGUUUAUCAGUAUUUCAUUGAGAUUUUUUGCGUCGAAGUUCAUCAGGGAUAUUGGACUGAAGUUUUCUUUUUGUUGUCGUAUCUCUGCCAGGUUUUGGUAUCAGGAUGAUGCUGGCCUCAUAAAAUGAGUUAGGGAGGAGUCCCUCCUUUUCAAUUGUUUGGAAUAGUUUCAGAAGAAAGGGUAUCAGCUCCUCUUUGUACCUCUGGUAGAAUUCAACUGUAAAUCCAUCUGGUCCUGGACUUUUUUUCAUUAGUAGGCUAUUUAUUACUGCCUCACUUUCAUAACUUGUUAUUGAUCUAUUCAGGGAUCCAACUUCUUCCUGAUUCAGUCUUGGGAGUGUGUAUGCAUCCAGGAAUUUAUCCAUUUCUUCUAGAUUUUCUAGUUUCUUUGCAUAGAGGUGUUUGUAGUAUUUGCUGUUGGUUGUUUGUACUUCUGUGAGAUCAGUGGUGGUAUCCUGUUUAUCAUUUUUUAUUGUGUCUGUUUGAUUCUUCUCUUAUUUUUGACAAAGCUGACAAAAAGAAGCAAUAGGGAAAGGACUCUCUAUUCAAUUAAUCCUACUGUAUAUCUGGCUAGCCAUAUGCAGAAAAUUGAAACUGUUCCUGUUUCUUAAUCCAUAUACGAAAAUCAACUUACGAUGGAUUAAAGACUUAAAUGUAAAACCCAAAAUUAUAAAACCCUGGAAUAGAAUAUAGGCAAUAUCAUUCUGGACAUAGGAAUGGGCAAAGAUUUUAUGAGAAAGACACCAAAAGCAAUUACAACAAAAGCAAAAAUUGGCAAAUGAGAUCUAAUUAAACUAAAGAGCUCUGCACAGCAAAAGAAACUACUGUCAGAGUGAACAGGCAACCAACAGAAUGGGAGAAAAUUUUUUCAAUCUAUCCAUAUGACAAAGGUCUAACAUCCAGAAUCUACAAGGAACUUAACAAAUUUACAAGAAAAAAGGAGCCCCAUUAAAAAGUUGGCAAAGAACAUGAACAGACACUUCCCAGAAGAUAUUCAUGUGGCCAAUAAACAUGAAGAAAAGCUCAACAUCACUGACCAUUAGAGACGUGCAUAUCAAAAUCACAAUGAGAUACCAUCUCAUGUCACAAUGGUGAUUAUUAAAAAGUCAAACAACAUGCUAGUGAGGUUGUAGAGAAAUAAGAACGCUUUUACACUGUUGGUGGGAAUGUCAACUAAUUCAACCACUGUGGAAGACAGUGUGGUGAUUCCUCAAGGAUUUAGAACCAGAAAUAUCAUUACUGCAUAUAGACCCAAAGGAAUAGAAAUCAUUCUAUUACAAAGAUACAUGCACAUGUAUGUUUAUUACAGCACUAUUCACAAUAGCAAAGACAUGGAAUCAACCCAAAUGCUCAUCAGUGAUAGACUGGAAAAAGAGAAUGUGGAACAUAAACACCAUGGAAUACUAUGCAGCAAUAAAAAGGAAUGAGAUCCUGUCCUUUUCAGGGACAUGGAUGGAGUUGGAAGCUGUUAUCCUCAGCAAACUAAUGCAGGAACAGAAAACCAACCACCACAUGUUCUCACUUAUAAGUGGGAGCUGAACAAUAGAACACAUGGGCACAGGGAGGGGAAUAACACACACUGGGGCCAGUCAGGGGGUGGGGGGUCAAGCUGAGGGAGAGCAUUAGAAAAAAUAGCUAAUGCAUUCUGGGCUUAACCCAUUUAUGCCUAGUGUUCCAUUUCUGGAAUGCUAAGCAUGUGGAAGUUCUUUAUAUCCUGCUCAAGGUCAUUGCCAAGGUCUGAUUUUUCACAUUCAACAAAUUGCAACCUCUGGCAUAAAUGGGUUAAUACCUAGGUGAUGAGUUGAUAGGUGCAGGAAACCACCAUGGCACAUGUUUAUCUAUGUAAGAAACCUGCACAUCCUACACAUGUACCCUGGAACUUAAAAAAUUUAAAAUAUAUAUGUAUAUAUAUUUAAUAUGGAAUUUUAAAAAUUACUAAUGAGUUCUUUUAUCUGAGUAAUUUUGCAUCAACAUGCUUUUAUUAUGGAAGAGAAGAUUCAGUGAGUACAAAAUUGCAGAUACAUGUGUCAGAAGAUCCCUGAAUAUAAUAAGGCUUAGUAUUCUGUGUCAUAAUUGCCUGUUUGUAUUCCUCUCUGGUCUUUAAACUUCAUUAGGGCAAGGAUCAACUCCAUCUUACUAACCAUUUGAUUCCCUAUGUAUUACACGAUAUAUGACCAAUAAUAAGCCUUCAAUAAAUACUUGUAAAAUAAAGAAUGUUAUGUAAUAUA